AGACAGCGCCGGGAAGAUGAGCACGGAAGGUGGUGGCCGUCGCUGCCAGGCACAAGUGUCCCGCCGCAUCUCCUUCAGCGCGAGCCACCGAUUGUACAGUAAAUUUCUAAGUGAUGAAGAAAACUUGAAACUGUUUGGGAAAUGCAACAAUCCAAAUGGCCAUGGGCACAAUUAUAAAGUUGUGGUGACAGUACAUGGAGAGAUUGACCCUGCUACGGGAAUGGUUAUGAAUCUGGCUGAUCUCAAAAAAUAUAUGGAGGAGGCGAUUAUGCAGCCCCUUGAUCAUAAGAAUCUGGAUAUGGAUGUGCCAUACUUUGCAGAUGUGGUGAGCACGACUGAAAAUGUAGCUGUUUAUAUCUGGGACAACCUCCAGAAAGUUCUUCCUGUAGGAGUUCUUUAUAAAGUAAAAGUAUACGAAACUGACAAUAAUAUUGUGGUUUAUAAAGGAGAAUAGCUAUUGGGGUUAGCAUUGCACAAAGCCCAGUUUCUUUCUGUGUUUGAAAAAGAUUUUGAUCCCCUUGGAAUAUUAAGAGGUCAACACGUGAUUGUUGUACGUACACAUUGUGCUCUGGAGUGCCUAUUUAUUGAAAUCAUUGUAAGACCUGUUAUAAAUUUAAGUCUAUUUAAAACUAAACUUGUAAUAUACAUCCUGAAAAUCAUUUAGAGAGUCUUUUAUUUAUAAAUUAAAAAUCACUUCAUUUUCACAAAAUGUUUUGGUGUGGGAUUAUUUGAAAGCAAAAGAAAUCUAAUUUUGUUUUCUCCAUUACCUCAUUUUAGUAUUAAUUUUUACUUGGUAUAAUAUACAUGGUUAAAAUGCUUAUGUGACUUCGAGUAGGUGAAUCUUAAAGAAAUAAAAUUCAAGUGACCACAAA